GGGCAGAGCAGGGAAGCCAACCUGAGCAAACACAGCAGCCCGAGUGUUCCCAAGGCCAAAAUGCUGAGAACGUCCACUCCUAAUCUGUGUGGUGGUCUGCAUUGCCGGGCCCCCUGGCUCUCUUCUGGCAUUCUCUGCCUCUGCCUCAUAUUCUUGUUGGGCCAGGUGGGCUUGCUGCAGGGACACCCCCAGUGCCUGGAUUACGGGCCCCCUUUCCAGCCCCCUCUGCACCUUGAGUUUUGCUCUGACUAUGAGUCCUUCGGCUGCUGUGAUCAGCACAAGGACCGCCGCAUCGCUGCCCGGUACUGGGACAUCAUGGAAUAUUUUGAUCUGAAGAGACAUGAGCUGUGUGGAGAUUACAUUAAAGACAUCCUUUGCCAGGAGUGCUCGCCCUACGCAGCCCACCUCUACGACGCCGAAAACACCCAGACGCCUCUCCGGAAUCUCCCGGGCCUCUGCUCUGAUUACUGCUCUGCCUUCCAUUCUAACUGUCACUCAGCCAUUUCCCUGCUGACCAAUGACCGCGGCCUCCAGGAGUCUCAUGGAAGGGACGGUACCCGCUUCUGCCACCUCCUGGACCUUCCUGACAAGGACUAUUGCUUCCCUAAUGUCCUGAGGAACGACUAUCUCAACCGCCACCUGGGCAUGGUGGCCCAAGAUCCUCAGGGCUGCCUGCAGCUCUGCCUGAGCGAGGUGGCCAACGGGCUGAGGAACCCCGUCUCCAUGGUCCAUGCUGGGGACGGCACCCAUCGCUUCUUUGUUGCCGAGCAGGUAGGAGUGGUGUGGGUCUACCUCCCUGAUGGGAGUCGCCUGGAGCAACCCUUCCUGGACCUCAAGAACAUCGUGUUGACCACCCCAUGGAUCGGGGAUGAGAGAGGCUUCUUGGGGUUGGCUUUUCACCCCAAAUUCCGCCACAAUCGCAAGUUCUAUAUUUAUUAUUCGUGCCUGGACAAGAAGAAGGUAGAAAAGAUCCGAAUUAGUGAGAUGAAGGUUUCUCGGGCUGAUCCUAACAAAGCUGACCUGAAAUCAGAGAGGGUCAUCUUGGAGAUUGAAGAACCAGCCUCAAACCAUAAUGGCGGACAACUUCUUUUUGGCCUGGAUGGCUAUAUGUACAUAUUCACUGGGGACGGGGGACAGGCUGGAGAUCCCUUUGGCCUGUUUGGAAAUGCUCAGAACAAAAGUUCCCUGCUGGGAAAAGUUUUAAGGAUCGAUGUGAACAGGGCAGGCUCACAUGGCAAGCGGUACCGAGUCCCCUCGGACAAUCCAUUUGUUUCUGAGCCAGGGGCCCACCCCGCCAUCUAUGCCUAUGGGAUCAGGAACAUGUGGCGUUGUGCUGUGGACCGAGGGGACCCCAUCACGCGCCAGGGCCGAGGCCGGAUAUUCUGUGGGGACGUGGGCCAGAACAGGUUUGAAGAGGUUGACCUCAUUUUGAAAGGUGGAAACUAUGGCUGGAGAGCAAAGGAAGGGUUUGCAUGUUAUGACAAAAAACUUUGUCACAAUGCCUCUUUGGAUGAUGUUCUGCCAAUCUAUGCUUAUGGCCAUGCAGUGGGGAAGUCAGUCACUGGAGGUUAUGUCUAUCGUGGUUGUGAAUCCCCAAAUCUCAAUGGCCUGUAUAUCUUUGGAGACUUCAUGAGUGGUCGACUUAUGGCUUUGCAGGAAGAUAGAAAAAACAAGAAAUGGAAGAAGCAGGAUCUUUGCCUGGGCAGCACCACGUCCUGUGCCUUCCCAGGGCUGAUCAGCACCCAUAGCAAGUUCAUCAUCUCCUUUGCUGAAGAUGAAGCAGGGGAGCUGUAUUUCCUGGCGACCUCUUACCCAAGUGCCUAUGCACCACGUGGAUCUAUUUACAAGUUUGUUGACCCCUCAAGAAUUCCAACCAGGCAGGUUAACAUCCUCACUCUAUGGAUAAAGAAACUGAAGGCUAGGCGAGCACCCCCAGGCAAGUGCAAAUACAAGCCAGUGCCCGUGAGAACCAAGAGUAAGCGGAUCCCGUUCAGACCACUCGCCAAGACAGUCUUGGACUUGCUAAAGGAACAAUCAGAGAAAGCUGCUAGAAAAUCUUCCAGUGCAACCUUAGCUUCUGGCCCAGCCCAGGGUUUGUCUGAGAAAGGCUCCUCCAAGAAGCUGGCUUCUCCUACAAGCAGCAAGAAUACAUUGCGAGGGCCUGGUACAAAGAAGAAAGCCAGAGUGGGGCCCCACGUCCGCCAGGGCAAGAGGAGGAAGAGCCUGAAAAGCCACAGUGGCAGGAUGAGGCCAUCAGCAGAGCAGAAGCGAGCUGGCAGAAGUCUCCCUUGACCUAUUGGUCAAGGUGGCCGACAGGGUGACGUGAGAGAGGAGAGCCACCUCAUCAAAUGAAAGUCACUGCUGAAUAAAGACCUUAGAAGUCUGGGAAGCCAGGGUAGAGGUGGGGCAGGGCGGUUUUCCUCUCCCUGGGAAAUCUUGCUGUCUACUGAAUAAAUAAAUGCACCUUCUCUGUAUGCAGUGCUUCUGUGGGAGACCAUAUCCCAGAUUGCUGGUGCACCUGGGUUAUGGUAAGCACUAGUCCAUGAGCCUGCUUGGAAUCACACUGGAUGUCUCCGUUUUGUCUUGUAAAUGCCUACAACCUGAG